GCACAUACCCCAUGUCUCACCACGAUGAUGGAGCUACAGUGGGACUUGGAAUCCAGAUGUGUGAAGGAUGGAGGGUUGAAGCCGCACUCAGCUUCCUGCCCCACCAGAGGAAGUGGGGAGAGACGGCAGGUGCAGUGAUGGCUGGCGGAGUCAUGGACAAGGAGUACGUGGGUUUUGCUGCCCUCCCCAACCAGCUGCACCGCAAGUCUGUCAAGAAGGGGUUUGACUUCACGCUAAUGGUGGCAGGGGAGUCAGGCCUAGGGAAAUCCACCCUCAUCAACAGCCUCUUCCUCACCAACCUCUAUGAGGAUCGCCAGGUGCCAGAGGCCAGUGCUCGCUUGACACAGACCCUGGCCAUUGAGCGCCGGGGCGUAGAGAUUGAGGAAGGGGGUGUGAAAGUGAAGCUGACCCUUGUGGACACACCUGGCUUUGGGGACUCAGUGGACUGCUCUGACUGCUGGCUUCCGGUGGUGAAAUUCAUCGAGGAGCAAUUUGAGCAGUACCUUAGGGAUGAGAGUGGCCUGAACCGGAAGAACAUCCAGGACUCCCGAGUCCACUGCUGCCUCUACUUCAUCUCACCCUUCGGCCGGGGGCUCCGGCCCCUAGAUGUGGCCUUCCUCCGGGCAGUACACGAGAAAGUCAACAUCAUCCCAGUCAUUGGCAAAGCGGAUGCUCUGAUGCCCCAGGAAACCCAGGCCCUCAAGCAGAAGAUCCGGGAUCAGUUGAAGGAAGAGGAGAUCCACAUCUACCAGUUCCCCGAAUGUGACUCUGAUGAAGAUGAAGACUUCAAGAGGCAGGAUGCAGAGAUGAAGGAAAGCAUCCCUUUUGCAGUCGUGGGAUCAUGCGAGGUGGUGAGGGAUGGCGGGAACCGGCCGGUGAGGGGACGCCGCUACUCCUGGGGGACCGUGGAGGUGGAGAACCCACAUCACUGCGAUUUCCUGAACCUGCGACGGAUGCUGGUGCAGACACACCUGCAGGACCUGAAAGAGGUGACGCACGAUCUGCUCUACGAGGGCUACCGGGCCCGCUGCCUACAGAGCCUGGCCCGGCCUGGGGCUCGCGAUCGAGCCAGCCGCAGUAAGCUUUCCCGCCAGAGCGCCACAGAGAUCCCGCUGCCCAUGCUGCCUCUGGCGGACACCGAGAAGCUGAUCCGCGAGAAAGACGAAGAGCUGCGCCGCAUGCAAGAGAUGCUGGAGAAGAUGCAGGCCCAAAUGCAGCAGAGCCAGGCCCAGGGCGAGCAGUCAGACGCCCUCUGAGGCCACGCCCCGCCCGGCCUUACCUCGGCUCCGCCUUCAGUCGGCCUCUUGUCCAAUCCCCGCGCCCCACACUGCCCAGCGCCCCCCGGGACCUCCGCGGGUGCCGCCCUCGCGCGGGCUAGGGGGAGGUUCUCCCAGCCUGAGUCCGUAGCCCCGCCCCGGCGCUGGUCCCGCCCACCCAGACACCGCCCACUUCCCGGCCCGGGGCCUGCACAAUCUCCGACCGCAUCACUGUCUUCCGGAGUCCCCCUUCUUCUCCCAGACUCUGUCUUCAAUAAAAACUGAGCUUCCCGCGGCCA